AAUAGGUGGCUUUUGACUACAGGUGAAUCUUCUGAUAAAGUAGUAUGAAAAUUAAAGAGACAGAGUCAACAGAGAAAGGUUCGGGCAAUAAGUAGAAGUGCUGAAGCCUUGGGGAGGAAGUGAUCUGCGUAAGUAUUACUUGUCAGUGAUCUAUCCAAGACACCAUGAAGAUCUUCUAAGGUCUGCACUCAAGACAGCACUGUAUGCCUUCAACUUGCUGUGUCCAUCUGUCUUCCUGGCUUCCUCAUCUCUCACAGUGAAUUUCUUUUGGUUUUCAAAACAUCACACAAAAGGCAGUAGGCUUCCAUUCUAGUUUUAUGGUGUCACCAAGUGCCUCCUGACUUGAGCAAGUCAGUUUUCCUCCUCCUGCCAUCCUCCUCCGACCUAAUGGCCUUCCAUUCAUGACAUCCUGUGAUUGUGUUUGUUCAUCCUCCACCCCCUUCAAAUGUCAUCAUUCCCUUACUUAAAUUUCUACAGCACGUGUUAUUAAUUUCCAAUUGUGUUGUGUGCUGACUUCUCUUAGGCACUCUAUUCCUUAAAAAUAGAGUCUAGGUUUUUCUUAUUUUAAAAUUCAUUUAUUCAAAAAUGUUGGUUUAAAACCUAUUAUGAGCCAGGGAGGGUUGUAGUGUAGGCAGUGUGUGUAGAGCAAAGAAGCAAACAAAAUCUUUGCCCUCUGGGAGCUAAGCUCUAGUGAGGGAUUUUAUAUAUAUAUAUAUAUAUAUAUAUAUACAUACACAUACACAUACCUUACUAGAGCUUAUAUAUAUAUAAUAUAUAUAAAAUAUUAAUCUGUUUAUAUUUAUAUAAAUAUUUAAAAUAUAUUUUACACAUAUUUCUUAAAAAAAGGAUAGAGGAUAUAUUAUAUUCUAUGCCAUAUAAUGUUAUAAAAUCAAUGAACUGAAUCACUCAGUUGUGUAUAUAUAUGUGUGCAUGUGUGUGUAUAUAUAUAUAUAUAUAUAUAUAUAUAUAUAUGUACACAUAGAAAGAGAGAGAGAAAGAAAGAGAAAGUCCUGGGGUAUGCGGUACGGGGAGGUACUAGUUUAUGCAGCAUACUGGUUAAGGGGUUAGAAGCUAUUUUAUGUAGUGUGCUUAGCUCUCUGUUGAGCUCUGGAUUCAUGUGUAUUCCUAAGGGUGCAGAGCCUAGAAAAUGGUAGCUGGUUAAUCAGUGCUUGUUGAAUAAUUAAUGAUUAAAUGAAUUUUUUGAUGACGAGUAUAGUGGGAAGAGAGAAGAGAGAAAAGGAGAGAGAGAGUGAAAUCUUUUAAAUUACACAAUGAUCCCCCAAAUGGUUUUUUUCUUAAGUCAUCAUGGUCAGAAGGAUAGACCUUGGAGAUCUGGCCCCAAAAACUUCACAUCCAGGUAAAUCCCAAUAUAAUUGGCCAGAUCCAGGAUGGGCAGAAAUCUGCAAGCUUGAAGCCAAUUCACAUAGUCUAUAGGUCACCUAAUAUGGUUGUGUUGAAAAUUCAAAUCCCCUCUAUGUUUCUACAGAAUGUUGUUUUCUUUCUCCAAGUCAUAUAUAGGUACUUUGAAUCUAAUUAAUAUUUUAAAUAAGUUUAUAUCAAAUAUGCUGUAACAUUGGAUUAUUAGGCUAUUAUCACAUUUGUUGAGAUAUCUUUUUCAAUCUAUCUGCUUUUUUAUAUUUUAUUUUUUGUAGUCUUAAGUUUUGCAUUUAUGUAAAAUUCAGUUAAAUAAAGAACACUUGCACCAAUGUUAUGGGAUUGGAACCUAAGGUAUAAAGUAUUUAUAUUUCCAUUAAGGCUAUGUUUAAUUUUCAAAUAAUAUCAAAUAAAUUUUGAUAUUAUUUGACAAGAUCUCUGAGCCAGAAUUCUUCAUUUCUAUUUUUUAUAUUUGGAAUAUAAUCCAAGUAUUUGGUCAUUGUCUAAAAUUGCCAAAGAAAAUUUCUGUCAGGAUAGGCUCCUCAUCUUCUGCCAGAAUUUCUGGGGUGAAUGCAGACUGGAACUCUUAGCUAAUGGACUGUGGCUUUAUUCUGUAUAUACUAUGUCCAUAAAAUCAAUGCACGACUUCAUUACUGAAAAUGGAAAGACAAAAUCAAAGCUGUGUGGUUGAAUUCAUCCUCUUGGGCUUUUCUAACUAUCCUGAGCUCCAGGGGCAGCUCUUUGUGGCUUUCCUGGUUAUUUAUCUGGUGACCCUGAUAGGAAAUGCCAUUAUUAUAGUCAUCGUCUCCCUAGACCAGAGCCUCCACGUUCCCAUGUACCUGUUUCUCCUGAACUUAUCUGUGGUGGACCUGAGUUUCAGUGCAGUUAUUAUGCCUGAAAUGCUGGUGGUCCUCUCUACUGAAAAAACUACAAUUUCUUUUGGGGGCUGUUUUGCACAGAUGUAUUUCAUCCUUCUUUUUGGUGGGGCUGAAUGUUUUCUUCUGGGAGCAAUGGCUUAUGACCGAUUUGCUGCAAUUUGCCAUCCUCUCAACUACCAAAUGAUUAUGAAUAAAGGAGUUUUUAUGAAAUUAAUUAUAUUUUCAUGGGCCUUAGGUUUUAUGUUAGGUACUGUUCAAACAUCAUGGGUAUCUAGUUUUCCCUUUUGUGGCCUUAAUGAAAUUAACCAUAUAUCUUGUGAAACCCCAGCAGUGUUAGAACUUGCAUGUGCAGACACGUUUUUGUUUGAAAUCUAUGCAUUCACAGGCACCUUUUUGAUUAUUUUGGUUCCUUUCUUGUUGAUACUCUUGUCUUACAUUCGAGUUCUGUUUGCCAUCCUGAAGAUGCCAUCAACCACUGGGAGACAAAAGGCCUUUUCCACCUGUGCCGCUCACCUCACAUCUGUGACCCUAUUCUAUGGCACAGCCAGUAUGACUUAUUUACAACCCAAAUCUGGCUACUCACCGGAAACCAAGAAAGUGAUGUCAUUGUCUUACUCACUUCUGACACCACUGCUGAAUCUGCUUAUCUACAGUUUGCGAAAUAGUGAGAUGAAGAGGGCUUUGAUGAAAUUAUGGCGAAGGCGAGUGGUUUUACACACAAUCUGACUGUGUUGAGAAGCCAUGUAAGAUUUAGUCACUGCAUGACUGUAUUCAAUCUAAAUUUAAUAAAUUUAGAUUCAUUAAGUUUGCAUUUUUUGGCAUGAGUAUGACUAAUUUAUUGUGUUCUCCAAGUUUGAUUGUAUAUCAGGAGCAUCUUUAUAUGUUAAUGUUUUUAGUUUUUUCACCAGUGCAUAAUAUUCCUUAAUAUUGAAUAUAACACAAUUUCAACAAUUUGUUUAGUAGUAGCCCUACUGAUGGUUAUUUUUUUGUCACAAUAGAUAAUACUAAAACAACCAGUUUUUAUAUAUUCAUAAAUUCUGGUGCUUUAAUUUUUACAGAAUAGCUUUCACAAAGUAGGUUUGAAGGGUCAAAACAAAUGUGAGUUUGCAAGUUUUCAUAGAUAUUACUGAGUUACUUUUUUAAAUGAUUUUAACAACUUCAGACUGACCUGAGCACCCAUCCUAUCCCUCUACUAUGUUGUAUGCCAAGAAGCCUACAAUAACGAGAUGAGAUUUUCUGCUUCUGUAGUGAAAAUCUGUUCCAUACAUAAGUAGGAAAGAACAGUUAUUUAUUGAGAGGAACACAAUGUCUCUACUCAGGGACCCAGAGAGUCUAUAAUUCAAAACUAGAUAUCUUCUGGUUAUUUUAGAAUAUAUAUUCCUCCAGUGUUUUGAGUAGAGAACAUCAUGUGAUCAUUUUUGAAGGUCAUUUAAAGUACGGCUGUCCUUUCCACUUAUAAACUAUAUUUUUUGAAACUUGGUCAAAUUUCUUUCAUAAGGCAAAAAUGCACCUCAUACAGGCCAAACAAUGUAUGAUUGUGUUUUUUUGUUGUGGGACAUAAAUAUGAUUACCUCAUUGUGCCUAUUUUCUAUUAUCCUUGGGUCAUAUCAAUAUUUAUGUGCAUCUUUCCAACAUAAAAUAAUCACAUAAUAGUCUUUCUAGUUAUAUAUAAAGAUGAAUAAUUAGACACAUUGCAACAUUGAAAUAUAACAUUUCAUUCUUGCUUCCUAUUUUAAUAUUGCUAUAAUAAAUAGAAAGGGUUCUUCUCAUUAAAUCUAUAUCAAAGGAGUUGACAACACCCUUCAUUUCUGCUCUGGGGGUGGAGGUGGGGUAAUAAAGCGGUUAGAACACUUCUACAAAACAAUCAUUCAUUGGAUGGAAAACCCUUCUUUUCUUCACUACUCCUUCUGCCAAAAAUAAAGGUGAAGUUGCAAAUCUAUUUGAAUUUCAAAAAAAGAGAGAAAUUUCAUGAGAAGAAGGCUGGAACCUUGUGGGUAAUGAUGCAGGACUUUUCUUCUCAGUCACUUUGGAAGCUGGGGACCCCUGACCGGCAACAGCCCACCUGGCAUGCCCCAGCUCACCUCUGUUAUAGCUUGUACCUGCAUUCAGCAGUUCCCAAGCUUUUGUACCACACCCAAGAAGAAUGAGGAUAUGCUGGGCAUUGAAGGGUAAGGAUGGUGGAGAAGAAUUUUACUGAAGGACAGAACAACUGUCAGCAGAGAGGGGAUAUGGGGGGUGGUUCCCCUACUGGAAGGCAGGAAAGCCCCACCAUGGUGGCUGGGUCCAGGACCUUUUAGGGACUCAAAAUGGGAAGUACAUGCUGGUUUGUGAGGUAUGCAAAAAGGUUAAAGUGAAGACACCACUCAAAGGUGGGCAUGACAGUGUAGAAAAACCAAUUAGGAAAGGGUAGGUAUAUGUAAAAUAGGUGAAGAGCGGGGAACAAUCAGAGGAAAGUAUGUGAAAUGGGAAGAUAAGUUCUCAAUCCGGUCCCAGAGUUUAACUUGCAGUUUGGCUUUCAGGCUUUAAACUGUCUUUUGUUUAGAGGUGGGGUUUCACCAGGAACCCACCCCAUCUGCCUAGGCAUUUGGCUGCCUCCUGUCGCUAUCAGUGAUAUCUGAAUGUUGUAUAAUACUGUUUUCAUUUGGGCACCAAACAGCCCUCAGCAAAAGCCUUUGAUUGGAUCCCAUCUCUUGAUAUCCUGAAAUUUCCUUCUGAUAGCUUUUAAAAGAACCAAUUAAGUAAGACUUAUGUAAAACGAACAAAUCAGCAAAGAAACAAACAAAGGAAGCUAAAUACAGAAAGUCUUUUUAGCCAUUCUUUAGUUCAUUUUGUUCAUUGAUUCUGUAAACCAAUUUUUUUCUUAAAAAAAAUUCUUUAUAAAAAUGUCUUAAGAGAGCUAAAUCUAAUGAAAUAGUCUCUGCUCUUGAAGGAUUUACAGUGUACUGGUCAUUAGAUGCUGGAAGGUUACUAUAUUUGACGCUUUCCUCUUUCAUUGCCUUUGUGAUAAAUAAAGCCUGGAUUGGCAAGAUGUUCAUGAAAUUACAAUAAGAAAUUAGGUCACUCUAAUUCUAAAUUUGUAUGUGUGUGUGUAUAUGCGUGUGUGAAUCCAAGUAUGUGCUGGGAAUUUAUACAUUUGUGAUGUUAUGUGAGGAGAUAGAAAUAAUCGCUAGUAAAUUUAGUCAUAGUUUAAAAUUUUUAUGUUAUUCUGAUGAAUAGAAAUUGUUAGUAUGCUUCACACAUAAUAGCCUAAUCAUAUCAUUUCUGCAUACUAUUCUUCAUGGUGAUUUUUAGUUAUAGUCACCGUGGCUGCUACUGCUGCUAGUUUUCUAGUUUAUGCCCAUUCUCCUUUUUCUUUAAUAGAGAAAACCCCAUUUUUGUUCUUUAAGUAGAAAAAAAAAACAAGUUUCUUAAGGGCAGUAAUGUAUCCAGUUAAUAACCAAUUUCCCAGUUUCUCUUUUGAACAAGGGUGGUUUGUGACACAGUUCUGACUAGUGAUAUAUAGGUGGACAUCCUUGAGUAGGGUGUCUAUGAAAACUCUUUAAAAAUGUGACUUAGUUAAUAAGGACUUUUUGCUCUUCAACCUCCUCCUUCCUUCUACCUGAAACAAGCCAUGAGGCUAGAGAUAGUGCAGCUAUCUUGCAAUGAGAGUUAAAGCAUGACUAGAAAAGCCAGGCCCUACAGAGGCCAAGUGGAAAGCUAGAGGGCCCCUGGGUCUGUGACGGCAUUGCGUAGUGACCUUAUCAUUCCUCUCCUGCCUAUUUGUUUACUGACUGUUACUUCAGAGAAAUAAACCUUGUCUUUGUUUAAUCCAGUAUUUGCUAGGUUUUCUGUUACAGCAUAACCCAAUCCAGA